GAGUUCGGGGCCAGCAGCCGUCUACCCGGUGUCGCGUUCUGUGUUGUGGCGGCCCUGGAUCCGGCGUCAGGGCGACCGGGCGGACGAGGUGGAGCCAGAGUCUGUCAGGCGGGUUGGUGAAGGGCGCGGGGCCGGGCACGGCGUUGGGAGUGCGCGGCAGGGACCGGCCAGGCGGGCUGCAGGCACCUCAGAGCCCGGGACACCCCCUCAACGUCCGCAGGCGCGAUGAAGGCACUGAUCUUAGUGGGGGGCUAUGGGACGCGGCUACGGCCGCUGACGCUGAGCACCCCGAAGCCACUGGUGGACUUCUGCAAUAAGCCCAUCUUGCUGCACCAAGUGGAGGCGCUAGCCGCGGCAGGCGUGGACCACGUGAUCCUGGCCGUGAGCUACAUGUCGCAGGUGCUGGAGAAGGAAAUGAAGGCACAGGAGCAGAGGCUGGGAAUCCGAAUCUCCAUGUCCCAUGAAGAGGAGCCUUUGGGGACAGCUGGGCCCCUGGCGCUGGCCCGUGACCUACUCUCUGAGACUGCAGACCCUUUCUUCGUCCUCAACAGUGACGUGAUCUGCGAUUUCCCCUUCCAAGCCAUGGUGCAGUUCCACCGGCACCAUGGCCAGGAGGGCUCCAUCCUGGUGACCAAGGUGGAGGAACCCUCCAAGUACGGUGUGGUGGUGUGUGAGGCUGACACAGGCCGCAUUCACCGGUUCGUGGAGAAGCCACAGGUGUUUGUGUCCAAUAAGAUCAACGCAGGCAUGUACAUCCUGAGCCCUGCAGUGCUGCAGCGCAUCCAGCUGCAGCCUACGUCCAUUGAGAAGGAGGUCUUCCCCAUUAUGGCCAAGGAGGGGCAGCUAUAUGCCAUGGAGUUACAGGGCUUCUGGAUGGACAUUGGGCAGCCCAAGGACUUCCUCACUGGCAUGUGCCUCUUCCUGCAGUCACUGAGGCAGAAGCAGCCUGAGCGGCUGUGCUCAGGCCCUGGCAUUGUGGGCAACGUGCUGGUGGACCCAAGUGCCCGCAUCGGCCAGAACUGCAGCAUUGGCCCCAAUGUGAGCCUGGGACCUGGCGUGGUGGUCGAAGAUGGUGUGUGUAUCCGGCGGUGCACGGUGCUGCGGGAUGCCCGGAUCCGUUCCCAUUCCUGGCUUGAGUCCUGCAUUGUGGGCUGGCGCUGCCGCGUGGGUCAGUGGGUACGCAUGGAGAACGUGACAGUGCUGGGUGAGGACGUCAUAGUUAAUGAUGAGCUCUACCUCAACGGAGCCAGCGUGCUGCCCCACAAGUCUAUUGGCGAGUCAGUGCCAGAGCCUCGUAUCAUCAUGUGAGGGGAUGCAGUGGGGCUGGCCGAGCCCCGGUUUUCCCAUCAGCAAGGGGAGUGCUGGCCUGACACAUCAGAAGACCCUGGACUUGUCAUUAUUUGUCUGGGGGGCACUGGGUGAAGCUGAAGCUGUUGGACACCUGCCUUCUCAUGUGGACAUCAUCUGGCAGGAUCCCUGCUGGGCACACCCCACAAACCCCACUCCCUCAAGAAGGGCCAGGGCCAGGGCUGUAUGGAAUAAUAAUUUAAUGCUCACUGUGGCCCUGACUGAAAGUCAAGCUCAGGCACAAUUAGGGCCAUGGCUGGGCUCCCACCAAUGAGGAUACAGGCAGGCAAGGAGGUUGGAUGUGGUGGUGUGGGAUACAGGAGAAGGGCAAAGGGAGCUCAUAAAUAGGGCCCAGCCUGGCUCUGGGUUCAAAGGUGGAGGUUCCAGGAUGGCACAGGCUGUGAGGGCUAGGCAGCUGAGGAGGUAGUACUCGUAUUGGCUCCCUUCUCCCAGUCCUCUACAGACACGAUGGUGGUUUUGCAGAAGAAGCAGUCCUUGUUGUUCAUCAGGUGCUGGUUGAUACAGGCUCUACAACAGGGGAGGGGAUGAGGACUGCCCUGCAUGUACCUACUGCUCUCCCCACCACCAAGCUGUGGGGCCCACUUACUUGCAGGACUUGUGGCCACAGGGCUGGAACACAGCAGAGAUGGGGUGGGCAUAGCAGAUGGGGCAGAGGUCCUCCUCACUGGUGGGCUGCAGGGAGGAGAGUGAAGGGUGGGCUGGAGUUGGAUGCCUGGCUAUGUGGAUGUCCGUUGUGCCUGUGUAGGAGUGCACACAUAUUCAAGUGGCAUGGACCUGUGCACCGUGUUCCCACUCACCAGGGAGGCAGCUGCUGCCUGGGCAGAUGCAGAGGUCAGGUGCGCCAGCAUCUGUUCCACUUGGGCCAGCUCAUCGGCACUGAUAUAAUCCGCAUCUGGGGAGUGGUAGGUAGUGUCAAGUCAGAGGUAGCUGAGGAUGUGAUGCCUCUUGAAUAUUCCCAGCCUAGGACUUUGCUGUUCUUAAGGCUCCUGACCCGACCCAGCCCCAGAUUUCCCUGACCUGCCCCACCAGCCCACUCACAGCUCUGCAGGGAGAAGCGCUUCCGGUCAGGGGCUGGCAGAGCAGUGCCAGGUGCUGGGGGCUCUGGCUGUCCCAGGAGAUAGCAUAUUGAGCGUAGCUGGAAGCAGGGAUCUGCCAGGAGCACUGAUGUGGCUUGCUCUCUCCUAGGUAGGGGAGGGUGCAAGGGCAGUCAGAAGGCUUGGGGCCUGGCUAAAAGUCUCUCUUGGGAUUGCCAAUGAGGAGUGCCAUGGCUCGUACAUGAUCACCCCCCCUGCAUCCUUUCCGUCUCCCUGCUUCCCAAACCCCAAGUCCUGUAUUCUAGUAAGGUGCCACACAGCCUGUUUUUUUUUUUUUUUUCUUGAGACGAGUCUCGCUCUGUUGCCCAGGCUGGAGUGCGAUGGCACGAUCUCGGCUCACUGCAACCUCCACCUCCCGGGUUCAAGUGAUUCUCCUGCUUUAGCCUCCCGAGUAGCUGGAAUUGCAGACGCCCACCACCACGCCCGGCUAAUUGUUGUAUUUUUAGUAGAGACAGGGUUUCACCAGGUUGGCCAGGCUGGUCUCGAAUUCCUGACCUCAGGUGAUCCACCUGCCUUGGCUUCCCAAAGUGCUGGGAUUACAGGCGUGAGCCACCGCGCCCGGCCUGGGGUACCACUUUAAGAAGGCUCAGGCGAACCACCUUAAGAUAGUGAGAGUCUGCCUGCCCCAUAAUAUUAUCAGUCCUUCAAAGUCACUUCAAAUAAACACUAACAGCAGCUUGGA